GGCGGCGGCUGCGGUGGCGGCAGCCGAGGCGAGCGGGGCGGGGGCGCGGGCGCGGCGCUCGGAGUCCGUUCGGGGCCGGAGGCGGUCGGGGCCGGGCCCGGGAAGCGCGAGGAGCGCGCGUAGCGCCGCCGGAGCCCGCCGCCCGGGACAUGGCCAAGGCGGGCCGUGCAGGUGGUCCUCCCCCGGGCGGCGGUGCCCCCUGGCACCUUCGAAAUGUCCUCAGUGACUCUGUGGAGAGCUCAGAUGAUGAAUUCUUUGAUGCCAGAGAGGAGAUGGCUGAAGGGAAGAAUGCCAUCCUCAUUGGGAUGAGCCAGUGGAACUCCAAUGACCUCGUGGAGCAGAUCGAGACCAUGGGGAAACUGGACGAGCAUCAAGGAGAAGGGACCGCGCCGUGCACAUCCAGCAUCCUCCAGGAGAAGCAGCGAGAACUGUACCGGGUUUCCUUGAGAAGACAGAGGUUCCCAGCCCAGGGAAGCAUCGAGAUCCACGAAGACAGCGAGGAAGGCUGCCCGCAGCGCUCCUGCAAGACACAUGUCCUCCUGCUGGUCCUGCAUGGGGGAAACAUCCUGGACACGGGUGCCGGGGACCCGUCCUGCAAGGCAGCCGACAUCCACACCUUCAGCUCCGUGCUGGAGAAGGUCACACGAGCCCAUUUCCCUGCUGCCCUGGGCCACAUCCUCAUCAAGUUCGUCCCCUGUCCUGCCAUCUGCUCUGAGGCUUUCUCGCUUGUCUCUCACCUGAACCCCUACAGCCACGAUGAGGGCUGCCUCAGCAGCAGCCAGGACCACGUCCCUCUGGCCGCCCUUCCCCUGUUGGCCAUCUCCUCCCCGCAGUACCAGGAUGCUGUCGCCACCGUCAUCGAGCGAGCCAACCAGGUCUACAGAGAGUUCCUGAAGUCCUCUGAUGGGAUUGGCUUCAGUGGGCAGGUGUGUCUCAUCGGGGACUGUGUGGGGGGCCUCCUGGCCUUCGAUGCCAUCUGCUACAGUGCGGGGCCCUCAGGGGACAGCCCUGCCAGCAGCAGCCGGAAGGGGAGCAUCAGCAGCACCCAGGACACCCCAGUCGCGGUGGAGGAAGAUUGCAGCCUGGCCAGCAGCAAGCGUCUCAGCAAAAGCAACAUUGACAUCUCCAGUGGGUUGGAGGAUGAGGAGCCCAAGAGGCCGUUGCCGCGGAAACAGAGCGACUCCUCCACCUAUGACUGCGAGGCCAUCACCCAGCACCAUGCCUUCCUCUCAAGCAUCCACUCCAGCGUGCUAAAGGAUGAGUCUGAGACCCCGGCGGCUGGGGGGCCGCAGCUCCCUGAGGUCAGCCUGGGCCGCUUUGACUUCGAUGUGUCCGACUUCUUCCUCUUCGGCUCGCCACUGGGCCUGGUCCUGGCCAUGCGGAGGACGGUGCUGCCUGGGCUGGACGGCUUCCAGGUGCGUCCUGCCUGCAGCCAGGUCUACAGCUUCUUCCAUUGCGCAGACCCCUCUGCCUCACGGCUCGAGCCACUGCUGGAGCCCAAGUUCCACCUGGUGCCGCCUGUCAGCGUGCCUCGCUACCAGAGGUUCCCACUGGGCGAUGGGCAGUCCCUCCUCCUCGCUGAUGCCCUACACACCCACAGCCCCCUCUUCCUGGAGGGCAGCUCCCGGGACAGCCCGCCACUUCUGGAUGCCCCUGCCUCGCCCCCUCAGGCCUCGAGGUUCCAGCGCCCAGGACGGAGGAUGAGCGAGGGGAGCUCCCACAGCGAGAGCUCGGAGUCCUCGGACAGCAUGGCACCCGUGGGUGCCUCCCGCAUCACAGCCAAGUGGUGGGGAAGCAAGAGGAUCGACUAUGCCCUGUACUGCCCUGAUGUCCUCACGGCCUUCCCCACCGUGGCCCUGCCCCACCUCUUCCACGCCAGUUACUGGGAGUCCACAGACGUGGUGGCCUUCAUCCUGAGACAGGUAAUGCGCUAUGAGAGCGUGAACAUCAAGGAAAGCGCCCGCCUGGACCCUGCAGCACUGAGUCCUGCCAACCCCCGGGAGAAGUGGCUUCGUAAGCGGACUCAGGUCAAGCUGAGGAAUGUCACGGCUAAUCACCGGGCCAAUGAUGUGAUUGCUGCUGAAGAUGGCCCCCAGGUCCUGGUGGGGCGGUUCAUGUACGGGCCCCUCGACAUGGUGGCUCUGACUGGAGAGAAGGUGGACAUCCUAGUAAUGGCAGAGCCAUCCUCAGGCCGCUGGGUACACCUGGACACAGAGAUCACCAACAGCAGUGGUCGCAUCACAUACAAUGUGCCGCGGCCCCGGCGCCUGGGGGUUGGUGUCUAUCCUGUGAAGAUGGUCGUCAGGGGCGACCAGACCUGUGCCAUGAGCUACCUCACGGUGUUGCCCAGGGGCAUGGAGUGUGUAGUGUUCAGCAUUGAUGGGUCCUUCGCGGCCAGCGUGUCUAUCAUGGGAAGCGACCCCAAGGUCCGGCCGGGUGCAGUGGAUGUUGUCCGGCACUGGCAGGACUUGGGCUACAUGAUCCUUUACAUCACGGGACGGCCGGACAUGCAGAAGCAGCGGGUGGUGUCGUGGCUGUCCCAGCACAACUUCCCACAGGGCAUGAUCUUCUUCUCCGAUGGGCUGGUGCAUGACCCGCUGCGGCAGAAGGCCAUCUUCCUGCGCAACCUCAUGCAGGAGUGCUUCAUCAAAAUCAGUGCGGCCUAUGGCUCCACGAAGGACAUCUCUGUCUACAGCGUGCUGGGCCUGCCUGCCUCCCAGAUCUUCAUUGUGGGCCGGCCCACCAAGAAGUACCAAACCCAGUGCCAGUUCCUGAGCGAGGGCUACGCCGCACACCUGGCCGCGCUGGAGGCCAGCCACCGCUCACGCCCAAAGAAGAACAACUCGCGCAUGAUCCUGCGCAAGGGCAGCUUCGGGCUGCACGCGCAGCCAGAGUUCCUGCGGAAGCGCAACCACCUGCGCAGAACCAUGUCAGUGCAGCAGCCCGACCCGCCCGCCGCCAACCCCAAGCCCGAGCGGGCCCAGAGCCAGCCCGAGUCGGACAAAGACCACGAGCGGCCGCUGCCGGCGCUCAGCUGGGCGCGUGGGCCCCCCAAGUUCGAGUCGGUGCCCUGAGGGGUGGGCUGUGCUCAGAGCAGGGAGCGGGGGGCCCAAUCAGGCUGCCUGCGGGGACGGGAGGGGGCUGCCCUCUCCCCGACACAGGCGUUUUCCUGCUUUUUCCCUCCCGUGUCUGUCCAGCAGUGUCCGACCAGAGCGGGGAGGGAUCCUGCCCGAGCCCGGGGGGCUCCCUGAGCUGCGACGGGGUGAGGUCCGGGGAUCUCGGUGCAGCCACUGCUGCCUCCCACGGGCCUGCGACCGCAAGCCCAAGUCAGGGUUCAUGUUUGUGUCAUCCUGGGGGCAGGCUUGCCCGGGGCUGAAGCGUUUGGGCAAAGUCGACCACCCUCCUGCGUCCCCAGGCUUCACAGCGAGCUAGGCAGGCCCUCAAGGGGGCAGCCCCAGCCUCGGCACCAAGCGCCGCUGGCAGGCACAGCCUCUGGGCUGUCUUGUGGAGGUGUGAGUGGCAUUUGUGCCCGCCCUUCCUGUGGUUUGGGUCACCAUUUUGGGGUUGGCGCUCUUAUGGCAAGAUGGCCACUUUCUGGGAGUGAGAGCACAUCCCCGGGCUCAUGUUACGCCGUCUCUGUCCACAGCCCUCGGGGGUGGGGUCUGGUGCUGACGGUCUGUCCUGCAGCUGUCCAUUGUCCCCAACCCCCGUUGUCCUCAGUGUCCUCACCAUUUCCCUGUGGCCCUGGAGGCCAGGGCUUCCUCUUCCCGGAGCCCUGCCUCAUGCCCUCCCUUGGGAGGCUGCAGCCUUGGGCUCUGGCUCAGCUGGGCUGGCUGUGAGCCCCUGAGCUGGUUGCUUGCCCUCUCUGGGCUCCGUCUUCCUUCUGUUAUUGGAGGGGUCCCCCUAGCUGAGAUUGGUGUGAGUCUUUGACUCCCAAGAUGUCCUGCAGUUUGGCCCAUUGAGGCUCUUCAGGCCUAAGGGUCCCUCCGAGUGUCCUGUGACCCACACCUUUCACACAGCCUGGGAGAGGGGGUCUGGGUGGGCUGGAAAGGAGGGGCUCUUAAAGGAGCCUCUCUGGGUGGGCUGGGAAGGGAUCCCUACUCCACGGAGAGGUGCAGCUGGUUUGCCUUGCACUGCGUGUCCCAGGGACAACCCACUCAAACUGGGUGUCCUAGGGACAACCCACCUCCCUCUCCUGCCAAAAGGUUACUGAUUGGGCUCCCCAUAACCCCAGCUCUGCCAGGACCCUUUUAUCCUUUUUGGCUCCCAGAGGCAUAGAGCUGAGAUUCCAGGGUUCUAGGGGUUCCUGGAAGUUUGGCUCCAACUGUUGUAUUCUCUUCCCUUUCCCCUGCUGCUCAGUUUGUGCCCAUAACCUCCUCCUGGGUAGUCCCCUGAGGUUGGCAGGACUUGGCCCUUCUGGGGCCCCUAAAGCCUGCUCAGGCCCUCCUGCUGCUGAACCUUGGCCUGGGCACUGCUUUCCUGCAUCCUGGAAAACCCCGACUCCCUGGCCCAGGCCCACACCUGCUGUGUGGGGCUGCCCACGUGGCCACUGAGCCCCCAUAGGCUGCCAUCAAGGCCGGUCCCAGCAAUUUCAGCCAGGCUGCCCCAGGGCCCAGACGUCUGUAUACACAGCAGGCACCUGUGUCAGCUCAGUGUCGCUUCUGCUCAAUGUCUACCUCUCGCGGCUCCCAUGCAGCCAGUGACGCUGCUGGUGGGGGCGGCUGGCACCGCCGUUGUGAAUUGCCUGGCAAAUUGGGUGCCCUCCUGGGGCUGGAGGGGUCUGGGCUCCUAACCCCCAUCCCUGCUCUCCCCACUAGAAAUGUGUCUUCAGUCUGCCAGCUCUUCUGCUCUACUUCCAGUGCUGCAUCCUGCACUCAAGCCCAGGGCUGCUGGCGAGUCUAUGGGGAGGAGUGCGGAUCAGGCUCAGCCUCAGCCUCAGCCUCAGCCUCCUCUAUGGUCCUGUCUCCUGGCGGUUCACAGGUGCCCAUCCCCCCUUUAACAUUUCACAGUUCUUGGCUUUCCAAAGGCACCAGCUCAUAUGGCAUAGCCACCCCAACCCUAAUCCUUCCCCCAAAUAUCCUGAUUUAAACUUGGGCAGACUUAGUCUGAUUCUUGAAAACUCUACCAUCUCCUUCUUGCAGAAGGCACUGGUUACACUAAAAUGAUAAAAUAAUUAGUAUGGGGUACUUUGCUCCCAGUUACAUUCCCUCUUCCCUGAGAACCCCAGGCUAGGCGAGAGAGGGAGAGGGAGAGAGAAAGAGAGAGAGGGAGAGAGAGAGAGAGAGAGGGAGAGAGAAAGAGAGAGAGAAAGAAAGGAAGACAGAGGAAAGAAAGGAAGACAGAGAGAGGAAGGCAGAGAGAGAGAGGGAGAAAGAAAGACAGGAAGGCAGAGAGAGAGAGAGAGAGAGAAAGGAAGACAGAGAGAGAGAGAGAGGAAGAGAGAGAGAGAGAGGAAGAGAGAGAGAGAGCUCAUGAGCCAGGAUCCCUGGGGAAUUUGAAGUCAGUGUGACCAGGGUUCUGUGGCUCUGGGGUCAGAGCUGGGACACAGGACCCAGCAGGAGGGCCACCACCCCUUCCUUUUGGAAACAGCUCUGGUUCCAAGCAGCAAUCAGGUAGGAGGAUCGGGGCUUUGGCUGAUGAUGCACACACAAGAUGCUGAUGGUGUACGGUGAGAUAUUGUGAACGCAACAACUGGAGCUGUAGUUGGCGUGUGUGAGUGUGUACCUGCGGUUCUGUUUAGUGGCGAGACAAGGUAUGUUUCAGUACUGCUUUCACGGCAACUGUGUAAUGCAUAUGCUCUUUCUACACUAGCGGUUUGCUCAGUUUUGUCUGUCCGGUUAAGUUGGAGAAAGAACCAAGUUGUGUUGUUCUCUGGAGGGGGUGCUGCUGCCUCUCCUUGAGUAGUUCUGUGACCCCCAAUCCAGCUGUUUUGUAGAGAAUCCUUCUAGCUUCUGGUAUGCCUGCUCUCCAGCAGCUGGAAACAGAUCUUCCUGCCUGACCAAAGCUCCUUGUUUCUUGCGUGGCAUGUUUGUUCUUCCCGAUCCGGUGGCUGUCGUAGCCGAGGGCCUGCCUGCCACCUUCCUUUAUCAUUUGCCCUGUUGGGGUUCAGGGUGCAUCCUUAGCCCAGGACCUGCUCUUCCAGCAUCAUGGGUUUUUUCCUAAAGAUCUCAACGGCUCCCUUGGGCUCCAUAAAAUAUUUCUUUUUUAAAAAAGCAGACUCCUUUCAUGCAUUGGGAUGAACGGCCCUCUUGUCUGGGUGCUGGGCUACAGCAAACAAAUGUGUUUGAAUCCCAGUAUUCCAGAGAUUCCUGGCGGUGGGCUGUCUAGAAGAGGCGAGGCUGGAUCUCACGGUUUUUAAACUGUAUUUUUACCCCUUUGGGACCCAUACCUGUGCCCUGGAGUCUUUCAUGAGGCACGUGGGUCCUCUGCAUCCUCACUCUCCCCCCUAGCCCAGGUGCAGCCCCGGGAGGGGUGCCCUGACCCCGCCUUAAACAACCAACUUUCCCACCGAAUCCCAUCGGCGGGCGGGGGGGGGGGGUUUGGGUGCCAAGUGCCCUGGAAACCUAUUGUCUUUUGGCUCAGCCAAAAGAAACAUUCCCUCCUUCCUUUCCUUCCGGGCUUGGGGGAAACCUUCGUAAAAAUCAUAGUUAGGGUUAAGUCCAAGCAGUGAGGCCUGACCUGGGCUCUGCUCUCCUUGUUGAGACACUAACAGGCAGUUGGGAGGAAAAUCUGCAUUUGACUCCACCCUCUUUGGGGCAAAGGAGAAACAGGUGACCCGAGGGGGGGCAGGCCAGAGGAGGGCGACUCGUGCACAGGGACCCCCACCCUUGGACCCCGCUGUCCUUUUCUAGUUGUUUACUUGGUGGUGGCAGCCAGUCUGACCUUGUCUGUGGUCUGACUGUUCCUAAGUGUGUAACUUUCAGUAUUAUCUGUGACAGAUGGUUCUGUGGUGAAAAAGGUUUAUUAUAUUCCUUAUGGCUGCCUUGUACAAAAUCCGUUAGAAACGCUAAUGUAAGAUAUCAGAUUUCUAACAAGACAAAAACAGCAUUAUGGAGUUAAAAGAUUUUUACAACUGGGUCUUGAUUUUGAUGUGAGCUGGUUUUUAGCUCUCAAAUGUUGUCACUUAAAUAAAAACCUUCUUUGCCUUUA